GGUGCUGAGCGCCGUCCUCAAGGAUCUCUACCACCUGCUGAAGCACGUAGUGUGUCUGGAGCCCGAUGACGUGGCCAAGCUCCAUGCCCAGUUGGCCCUAGAAGAGCUGGAUGACAUCAUGAAAAACUUCCUGUUCCCUCCACAGAAGCUGGAGAAGAAGAUCAUGGUCCUGCCGUAGACCUGGCUCCAAGGACGUGGAGGAGGCAGGCAGGGCCAGGCACCCAGAGCCGUGCCCAGGUCUUCCAGCAGGUGGCCCUGCUGCCUCUUGAGUGCUGGCAGCAUGGCUGACCCUCGGGGUGGUUUUAUGGUGCAGGUCACUUGGGUCUUCAGGGUCCCUUCCGAGGGCAUGUGUUCAGCACUCCCGCGUUCAGCCUGAGGGGUGUACAGUUAAGAGAAGACAGUUACAGAUCUCAUUAAUCUACAUUUUUCACUGUCCUCUAGCAUUGAAAGAAGGAUGUCUACCUGGUGAAAGUAUAUUUUAACAUGACUGAUGGAAUUUCACUAAUUGCCCACUCUCUUGGAACUUGAGGAGAAGCGGUUGGCCACCCAUAUGUCACCUAGCUCUAUAUUCUUUCAGGCUGAGAUUCUUCUUCAGGAAAAUGAGGAGCAGAACUGGCCACCCUUGGCUGCUCAAGAGGCAUUUCAGAGUAGGAGAUGCAGUUGGAGGUGGGGAGGGGAAGGAAAUAGUUAUCAAAUAAUGCAAAAUGGAAUAAAGUUAUCUUGGAUGGAAAGAACAGGGCUAAAUCUGGUCCUCUGGUGUCGAGAUGGAAAACUGUGGAGUUGAAGAGGCUCUGAUGCCCAGAAAGGACAAUCAAGCUGGUUGACUCUUCCAGAGAAGAAGGAUGGUGUCUUGCUCUGUCGCCAGGUUGGAGUGCAGUGGCGCAAUCUCGGCUCACUGCAACCUCUGCCUCCCGGGUUCAAGCGAUUCUACUGCCUCAGCCUCCCGAGUAGCUGGGACUACAGGUGCACACCACCAUGCCCAGCUAAUUUUUGUAUUUUUAGUAGAGGUGGGGUUUCACCAUGUUGACCCGGAUGAUCUCGAUCUCCUGACCUCAUGAUCCACCCACCUCAGCCUCCCAAAGUGCUGGCAUUACAGGCGUGAGCCACCGCGCCCAGCCUAAUUCAUACGAUUUUAAAGAAAACAACAACAUAAAUGCAGGAAGGUUUUGCUGCCUUGGCUUUCGGGAGCCCCCUAGACAGCGAACUGCCCCUUCGCGUGCAGAAGUCGGGGAAGAGUGCUCUCAGCUCGCCUUCCUUGCAGGAUGCCGGUGCAGCUGACGACAGCCCUGCGUGUGGUGGGCACCAGCCUGUUUGCCCUGGCAGUGCUGGGUGGCAUCCUGGCAGCCUAUGUGACGGGCUACCAGUUCAUCCACACGGAAAAGCACUACCUGUCCUUCGGCCUGUACGGCGCCAUCCUGGGCCUGCACCUGCUCAUUCAGAGCCUUUUUGCCUUCCUGGAGCACCGGCGCAUGCGACGUGCCGGCCAGGCCCUGAAGCUGCCCUCCCCGCGGCGGGGCUCGGUGGCACUGUGCAUUGCCGCAUACCAGGAGGACCCUGACUACUUGCGCAAGUGCCUGCGCUCGGCCCAGCGCAUCUCCUUCCCUGACCUCAAGGUGGUCAUGGUGGUGGAUGGCAACCGCCAGGAGGACGCCUACAUGCUGGACAUCUUCCACGAGGUGCUGGGCGGCACCGAGCAGGCCGGCUUCUUUGUGUGGCGCAGCAACUUCCAUGAGGCAGGCGAGGGUGAGACGGAGGCCAGCCUGCAGGAGGGCAUGGACCGUGUGCGGGAUGUGGUGCGGGCCAGCACCUUCUCGUGCAUCAUGCAGAAGUGGGGAGGCAAGCGCGAGGUCAUGUACACGGCCUUCAAGGCCCUCGGCGAUUCGGUGGACUACAUCCAGGUGUGCGACUCUGACACUGUGCUGGAUCCAGCCUGCACCAUCGAGAUGCUUCGAGUCCUGGAGGAGGAUCCCCAAGUAGGGGGAGUCGGGGGAGAUGUCCAGAUCCUCAACAAGUACGACUCAUGGAUUUCCUUCCUGAGCAGCGUGCGGUACUGGAUGGCCUUCAACGUGGAGCGGGCCUGCCAGUCCUACUUUGGCUGUGUGCAGUGUAUUAGUGGGCCCUUGGGCAUGUACCGCAACAGCCUCCUCCAGCAGUUCCUGGAGGACUGGUACCAUCAGAAGUUCCUAGGCAGCAAGUGCAGCUUCGGGGAUGACCGGCACCUCACCAACCGAGUCCUGAGCCUUGGCUACCGAACUAAGUAUACCGCGCGCUCCAAGUGCCUCACAGAGACCCCCACUAAGUACCUCCGGUGGCUCAACCAGCAAACCCGCUGGAGCAAGUCUUACUUCCGGGAGUGGCUCUACAACUCUCUGUGGUUCCAUAAGCACCACCUCUGGAUGACCUACGAGUCAGUGGUCACGGGUUUCUUCCCCUUCUUCCUCAUUGCCACGGUUAUACAGCUUUUCUACCGGGGCCGCAUCUGGAACAUUCUCCUCUUCCUGCUGACGGUGCAGCUGGUGGGCAUUAUCAAGGCCACCUACGCCUGCUUCCUUCGGGGCAAUGCAGAGAUGAUCUUCAUGUCCCUCUACUCCCUCCUCUAUAUGUCCAGCCUUCUGCCGGCCAAGAUCUUUGCCAUUGCUACCAUCAACAAAUCUGGCUGGGGCACCUCUGGCCGAAAAACCAUUGUGGUGAACUUCAUUGGCCUCAUUCCUGUGUCCAUCUGGGUGGCAGUUCUCCUGGGAGGGCUGGCCUACACAGCUUAUUGCCAGGACCUGUUCAGUGAGACAGAGCUAGCCUUCCUUGUCUCUGGGGCUAUACUGUAUGGCUGCUACUGGGUGGCCCUCCUCAUGCUAUAUCUGGCCAUCAUCGCCCGGCGAUGUGGGAAGAAGCCGGAGCAGUACAGCUUGGCUUUUGCUGAGGUGUGACAUGGCCCCCAAGCAGAGCGGGUAAAGUGCAAUGGGUAAGGGAGGGAAGGGGAAUGGAAGAGAAAAGACAGGGUGGGAGGGAGGAGGGAGUGCUGUGUUUUAGUCUCUUAAUGGUCCAAAGGACAAAUCUAAAAUGCAAAGAACGGUGAUGUAGUAUGGCCUGACAGCUCUGUUUAGAGGAGGCAACACUGAUCCCCCAGAUGCAGGGCUGCAGGGGAUUCUGUGUUUUCAGACUGCCUGUCUGCUUGCAUCUGCACAUAGGCAGUAGCCUCCUCCUGGGCUCCAGAGGGCACUCAGAAGUUGUGCUAAACCAAGUUAAGUCCCAUUCAGUGGCAACUUGUGAUAGGUACCUGAGUGACGGCAACCUGCGGAAGGAGGUUCUCCCAGCCCAUCUGAACACAACCAGAGGUGGCAGGAGAAUUUCUACUGAGCGAGCUGGGCCGGUUAGUGUAUGUCACCCCCACCCCACCCCUAAGUAGUCAUCAAUGCAAUAAGAUUGCGCCUGAGAUACAAGGCCCAGAAGCCUGAUCUUUGGGCAUCAGAAAACAGGGUCCAGGAAUGGUGCUUUAUGUGAGAUACCCCACUCCACAUCAACAUUCCAGGGAUGAGCCAAACCAGCAGGGAGUUAGCACUGAACUGCUUUUAAAAGUGCACAUUAAAAAGGAAAGUUUGCCAGGAGGAACAAAGAGAUUGUGGUGGUGCUAAAGGAGGCCAUAAGCUACACAGAGGCCUUGGGUGUUCCACCUGGAAACUGCUCAGACGUCUAGAUGGGUUCUUAGCUUGUCUGUGAUCUCUGCUGGGGAGAUAAAAAGAUUAAGCCCCAACAUGUUCAGAAAAGAAGUGAAGUCUUGGGUAUUUUAACCUGUAUACUCUUGAAUUCCUCUCAAAUUCAGCUCUGAUCUGAGGCUAAGACACACUCCCCACUUCACUUUCUUCAAAGCCACAUUUUUUGAGGUAUCACUGCAGUCACCUCUUCUACCCUCAUCAUCAUAGGUAAGGUUUUCAAGGUGGCAAUUGGGGCGGAGCCCCGGCUCUUAUAGAAGCUUCAGCAGGAGGCAAGCGUGUUCUCAGCACAUAUGGGAACUAUGAGGAGCCUCUGAUCAAAUUGGCUACAAUCUUGGAGCUGCUUGGACGGAUUCCUUGGCAGCCGGGUUAGCAUGUGUGACUUUCAGGCUACUGUUCUUGACAAUCAUCUCCAAUGGAAAGCUUUUCAGUGUUCCCAAAGUGAACUCUCAAAUCCAAAAUGGUUAUCUUUGAGACCAUCCAUUCUCCUCAGUGGCUUCUCCAGGGAAUUCUUACAGCCAAGUUGUGACAGUCACUGCAUUUGCCUGCUUCUUUCCAGAAACCAAACUAGGAGAUGAAACUGGUUCCUACAUCCUAAGGUUCUUGCUUUCUCUCUCAUGCCUCCUGAGGCUGUUUUUGGCUGUUUUCCCUCUGCUGCUUUUGGGGAAUGAGGGGAAGCCAUUUUCCAGUGACUUGCAAUCCAGGCUGUUCUCAGCGUUUUGAGUUUAAAACCUGGGAUCCUGACUAAGCCUUUGACUUAAGGGUUGCUUGCUUGCCCUCCAAAUGUCCUUUCUCAGAGGGGCCAGCUAACCCGUGCAGAACCAGCACUAAGGUGGACAGCAGACAAGAGGGCAAGCCUCUAGUGUACCAAGUGCUUCCUACAAAGACGCAAGGUGUGCUCUGAGCCACAGAUGGGCAAACCCUGGUGCUUUCCUUCAUCUCCCACGAACUCAAGGGUUUUCCAGGUGUAGCUAACAGUUGCCACAUCACACAGACCUCGAGUUUCUGGUAAGACUGCUGGUUGACAUCAGACCCAACCCAUGAAGGCUGGAAGGCAGCAGGCAUUUGCUAAGGCAGCUGAUCCAGGCAAUCGUUCUGCUGGCCAAGAAGUUAAACUAUUUUGAGCAUUAGAAUGGAGGAAAUCCGGUCAGCCAAGUGCAGAGUUCAGACUUCGCUAAGGGCUUGUUUUUCUUCAGCAUUUACUUGAAGAUUAAUGUAGGAUGACAGGCUCUCCUGGCUGUCCUACCAUCAGCUCUGCCUUGCACUGUGGUCGUCAACUUUCCUCAAAUCAAAAACAGGCAGGUACAGGUAGUGGGCUCACAACGUUUGACCUCGACUGGUUUUUCUAAGUUAUUUUGUACAUUUUUCAGCAGCAAAACCAAACUGGGUCUUCAGCUUUAUCCCCGUUUCUUGCAAGGGAAGAGCCUUUAUACAAUUGGACGCAUUUUGGUUUUUCCUCAUUGAGAAUUCAAAUCCUCUUUUGUAUUGUUUCUACAAUAAUUUGUAAACAUAUUUAUUUUUACCUGCUUUUUUUUUUUUUUUUAAUUUUCAGGUCAAGUUUUUUAUACUGCACUUAUUUGUCAAAAUAAAGAUUCUCACAUAUGCCGGUUA